ACUCCCAGGACUCCCGGCCGGGGUAGCUCUUCACUCCUCAGCGCGACGUCGUGUCGAGUUCCCAAAAAGCUCCGCAGGGGCUGUAGGGAGGUUGAAGCAUAUGAAGAAAACACCAGCCUUGAACAGAUACGUAGCAGGAAAAGCGAGGAUCUUACAAGCCUGCUGAAAGGCUCCUGGGGACAUCCAGGGGUCCUGAGACCACAGUUUGAGAAAGCUGAUUUAACCAUUUUUGGAUUGGUGGGCUGUUAGGUUGUUUAAAAUUUUACACUGUUACAACCCUUGCAACAGUGAAAGUUCUUUGUGAUGUUUUCUGGUGUAUGCGUGCUAGUGUUUUUUCUGUAAGUAGAAUUGCUAGGUCAUAGAGUUUUGCUUUUUUUUAAGUUUGUUAAACACAUUACUUUUGAUGCCUGUAUAAUUUGCUUUUGUGCACUAAUGUUGGUGUUUAGAUUGUUUCAACUAAUGAUUUGGUGAAAUAUCUUUGCAUGUUUUUAGUUGUUUUGAAUUAUUUUCUUUUUGAGGGGGCUGGGGGGAGUCCAGUAAAAACCAGACAACUGCCAGAUACAUUUUAAGAGAGCUUUAACACAUGGAUUCUUUUCUAAAAUUUCUAAAAAGAUAAUUGUUAGAUCAAAUAUUAGGAAUCUUUCUCAGGCUAUUGGUACAUAUUGUCACAUUGUUUUCAUGGGAGAUAGUACCAGUUUGUUUCCUGUCAGCAGUGUCUGACAUGCUUUAAAAAAAAAAAUCACACCCUUACCAACAUCGAGUACUUUUAUUAUUUUAAAAAAUUGUUUCAAUUUAGCAGGCAAUAAAUGGUAUAUGUUCUAAUUCUCAUUACUUUGAUAGUGCACUGAAUAAUUUUCAUAAUCUUACUAGUUGUCUGUUGAUGUUAUUUGCUCGUUUAUAGUCCAGUAUCCAAGUGUUUUUCUAACACAUUUUUAUCUUCUUAAAUAUAUUGUAAGGAAACGUGCUGUACUUUGUUUGUUUGUUUUUUAAGACAGAGUCUCGCUCUUUCGCCAGGCUGGAGUGCAGUGGCGUGAUCUCGGCUCACUGUAACCUCUGCCUCCCGGGUUCAAGGGAUUCUCCUGCCUCAGCCUCCUGAGUAGCUGGGACUACAGGCACGCGCCCCCAUGCCCAGCUAAUUUUUGUAGUUUAGUAGAGACAGGGUUUCACCAUGUUGGCCAGGAUGGUCUCGAUCUCCUGACCUUGUGAUCCGCCUGCCUCGGCCUCCCAAAGUGCUGGGAUUGCAGGUACGAGCCACCUCACCCGACCUUAGGAAACGUGCUGUACUUUUUUUUAAAGGAAAACAACAAAAUUAUGUUUUCUCGGUUUACAAGAGCACAUGCCUUUUUUUUUUAAAUUUAUUUUAUUUUUAUUGAUUUAGUUUUUUGAGAUGGAGUCUCGCUGUGUCGCCAGGCUGGAGUGCAGUGGCACCAUCUCGGCUCACUGCAACCUCCGCCUCCUGGGGUUCAAGCGAUUCUCCUGCUUUAGCCUCCCAAGUAGCUGGGGCUACAGGCACGUGCCACCACGCCCAGCUAAUUUUUUUUUUUUUUUUUUUUUGUAUUUUUAGUAGAGACAGGGUUUCACCAUGUUGGCCAGGAUGAUCUCGAUCUCUUGACCUUGUGAUCUGCCCACCUCAGCCUCCCAAAGUGCUGGGAUUACAGGCAUGAGCCACCACGCUGGCCAAGUAUAUGCUUAUAAAAAAAAAGUAAAAUAGUAUGAAGACAUAUCAUGUAGCUCUGAAAGGCUUACAUAAUCCCAUUCCUAGAUUUAUAGUAUUACUAACAUCAUUAAUGUUUGUUCCUUCAUAUUUUUUUACUAUGCAUUUGUUAAUUUUUUUUACAACUUAUUUGUAAAAAUAGGUUUGCACUAUGCAUAAAGUUUUGUGAUUUGAUUUUCUUUCAUUUAACAUUAUAUAUUGGAUAUUUUUCUACUGAAGUACAUAUAACUGGGCAAAGUUUUAUCCUGAGUGGUUUUAGGAACAUGAGUUGUGAUCUUUAGUUAUCUGAUGGCAGGCUCUUGUCCUCUUCUAAAUAUAUUCUCUUCCUAGGUGAUCUCAUCCAUUAACAGCUGUGUGUUGCCAGUUCCCAAAUCUUUAUCUAUCUCAGACUUCUCUCCUGCAUUCCAGAUUCUUAUAUUCAGCUGCCUUUUGGAUAUCUCUCCCAGGAUGUUCUCAAGGCAUACAAGAAUUAAAUUCUGAAUAAGUCUGCAGGUAGGAUGGACAGUUAUUUUAAAGCAGCUGUCAGUGACUUGGACAAACUCCUUGAUGAUUUUGAACAGAACCCAGAUGAACAAGAUUAUCUCCAAGAUGUACAAAAUGCAUAUGAUUCUAACCACUGCUCAGUUUCUUCAGAGUUGGCUUCCUCACAGCGAACUUCAUUGCUCCCAAAAGACCAAGAGUGCGUUAAUAGUUGUGCCUCAUCAGAAACAAGCUAUGGAACAAAUGAGAGUUCCCUGAAUGAAAAAACACUCAAGGGACUUACUUCUAUACAAAAUGAAAAAAAUGUAACAGGACUUGAUCUUCUUUCUUCUGUGGAUGGUGGUACUUCAGAUGAAAUCCAGCCGUUAUAUAUGGGACGAUGUAGUAAACCUAUCUGUGAUCUGAUAAGUGACAUGGGUAACUUAGUUCAUGCAACCAAUAGUGAAGAAGAUAUUAAAAAAUUAUUGCCAGAUGAUUUUAAGUCUAAUGCAGAUUCCUUGAUUGGAUUGGAUUUAUCUUCAGUGUCAGAUACUCCCUGUGUUUCUUCAACAGACCAUGAUAGUGAUACUGUCAGAGAACAACAGAAUGAUAUCAGUUCUGAAUUACAAAAUAGAGAAAUCGGAGGAAUCAAAGAAUUGGGUAUAAAAGUAGAUACAACACUUUCAGAUUCCUAUAAUUACAGUGGAACAGAAAAUUUAAAAGAUAAAAAGAUCUUUAAUCAGUUAGAAUCAAUUGUUGAUUUUAACAUGUCAUCUGCUUUGACUCGACAAAGUUCCAAAAUGUUUCAUGCCAAAGACAAGCUACAACACAAGAGCCAGCCAUGUGGAUUACUAAAAGAUGUUGGCUUAGUAAAAGAGGAAGUAGAUGUGGCAGUCAUAACUGCCGCAGAAUGUUUAAAAGAAGAGGGCAAGACAAGUGCUUUGACCUGCAGCCUUCCGAAAAAUGAAGAUUUAUGCUUAAAUGAUUCAAAUUCAAGAGAUGAAAAUUUCAAAUUACCUGACUUUUCCUUUCAGGAAGAUAAGACUGUUAUAAAACAAUCUGCACAAGAAGACUCAAAAAGUUUAGACCUUAAGGAUAAUGAUGUAAUCCAAGAUUCCUCUUCAGCUUUACAUGUUUCCAGUAAAGAUGUGCCGUCCUCAUUGUCCUGUCUUCCUGCGUCUGGGUCUAUGUGUGGAUCAUUAAUUGAAAGUAAAGCACGGGGUGAUUUUUUACCUCAGCAUGAACAUAAAGAUAAUAUACAAGAUGCAGUGACUAUACAUGAAGAAAUACAGAACAGUGUUGUUCUAGGUGGGGAACCAUUCAAAGAGAAUGAUCUUUUGAAACAGGAAAAAUGUAAAAGCAUACUCCUUCAGUCAUUAAUUGAAGGGAUGGAAGACAGAAAGAUAGAUCCUGACCAGACAGUAAUCAGAGCUGAGUCUUUGGAUGGUGGUGACACCAGUUCUACAGUUGUAGAAUCUCAAGAGGGGCUUUCUGGCACUCAUGUCCCAGAGUCUUCUGAUUGUUGUGAAGGUUUUAUUAAUACUUUUUCAAGCAAUGAUAUGGAUGGGCAAGACUUAGAUUACUUUAAUAUUGAUGAAGGCGCAAAAAGUGGCCCACUAAUUAGUGAUGCUGAACUUGAUGCCUUUCUGACAGAACAGUAUCUUCAGACCACUAACAUAAAGUCUUUUGAAGAAAAUGUAAAUGACUCUAAAUCGCAAAUGAAUCAGAUAGAUAUGAAAGGCUUAGAUGAUGGAAACAUCAAUAAUAUAUAUUUCAAUGCAGAAGCAGGAGCUAUUGGGGAAAGUCAUGGUAUUAAUAUAAUUUGUGAAAUAGUUGAUAAACAAAAUACAAUAGAAAAUGGCCUUUCUUUAGGAGAAAAAAGCACUAUUCCAGUUCAACAAGGGUUACCUACCAGUAAGUCUGAGAUUACAAAUCAAUUAUCGGUCUCUGAUAUUAACAGUCAAUCUGUUGGAGGGGCCAGACCUAAGCAAUUGUUUAGCCUUCCAUCAAGAACAAGGAGUUCAAAGGACCUGAAUAAGCCAGAUGUUCCAGAUACAAUAGAAAGUGAACCCAGCACAGCAGAUACCGUUGUUCCAAUCACUUGUGCUAUAGAUUCUACAGCUGAUCCACAGGUUAGCUUCAACUCUAAUUACAUUGAUAUAGAAAGUAAUUCUGAAGGUGGAUCUAGUUUCGUAACUGCAAAUGAAGAUUCUGUACCUGAAAACACUUGCAAAGAAGGCUUGGUUUUGGGCCAGAAACAGCCUACUUGGGUUCCUGAUUCAGAAGCUCCAAACUGUAUGAACUGCCAAGUCAAAUUUACUUUUACCAAACGGCGACACCAUUGCCGAGCAUGUGGGAAAGUAUUUUGUGGUGUCUGUUGUAAUAGGAAGUGUAAACUGCAAUAUCUAGAAAAGGAAGCAAGAGUAUGUGUAGUCUGCUAUGAAACUAUUAGUAAAGCUCAGGCAUUUGAAAGGAUGAUGAGUCCAACUGGUUCUAAUCUUAAGUCUAAUCAUUCUGAUGAAUGUACUACUGUCCAGCCUCCUCAGGAGAACCAAACAUCCAGUAUACCUUCACCAGCAACUUUGCCAGUCUCAGCACUUAAACAACCAGGUGUUGAAGGACUAUGUUCCAAAGAACAGAAGAGAGUAUGGUUUGCAGAUGGUAUAUUGCCCAAUGGUGAAGUUGCAGAUACAACAAAAUUAUCAUCUGGAAGUAAAAGAUGUUCUGAAGACUUUAGUCCUCUCUCACCUGAUGUGCCUAUGACAGUAAACACAGUGGAUCAUUCCCAUUCUACUACAGUGGAAAAGCCAAACAAUGAGACAGGAGAUAUUACAAGAAAUGAGAUAAUUCAGAGUCCUAUUUCUCAGGUUCCAUCAGUGGAAAAAUUGUCUAUGAACACAGGAAAUGAGGGGUUACCUACUUCUGGUUCAUUUACACUAGAUGAUGAUGUUUUUGCAGAAACUGAAGAACCAUCUAGUCCUACUGGUGUCUUAGUUAACAGCAAUUUACCUAUUGCUAGUAUUUCAGAUUAUAGGUUACUGUGUGAUAUUAACAAGUAUGUCUGCAAUAAGAUUAGUCUUCUACCUAAUGAUGAGGACAGUUUGCCCCCACUUCUGGUUGCAUCUGGAGAAAAGGGAUCAGUGCCUGUAGUAGAAGAACAUCCAUCUCAUGAGCAGAUCAUUUUGCUUCUUGAAGGUGAAAGCUUUCAUCCUGUUACAUUUGUCCUAAAUGCUAAUCUACUCGUGAAUGUCAAAUUCAUAUUUUAUUCCUCAGACAAAUAUUGGUACUUUUCAACCAAUGGAUUGCAUGGCUUGGGACAGGCAGAAAUUAUUAUUCUAUUGUUAUGUUUGCCAAAUGAAGAUACUAUUCCUAAGGACAUCUUCAGACUAUUUAUCACCAUAUAUAAGGAUGCUCUAAAAGGAAAAUACAUAGAAAACUUGGACAAUAUUACCUUUACUGAGAGUUUUCUCAGUAGCAAGGAUCACGGAGGAUUCCUGUUUAUUACACCUACUUUUCAGAAACUUGAUGAUCUCUCAUUACCAAGUAAUCCUUUUCUUUGUGGAAUUCUUAUCCAGAAGCUUGAGAUUCCCUGGGCAAAGGUUUUUCCUAUGCGUUUAAUGUUGAGAUUGGGUGCAGAAUAUAAAGCAUAUCCUGCUCCUCUAACAAGCAUCAGAGGCCGAAAACCUCUUUUUGGAGAAAUAGGACACACUAUUAUGAACUUACUUGUUGACCUUCGAAAUUACCAGUAUACCUUGCAUAAUAUAGAUCAACUGUUGAUUCAUAUGGAAAUGGGAAAAAGCUGCAUAAAAAUACCACGGAAAAAGUACAGUGAUGUAAUGAAAGUACUAAAUUCUUCCAAUGAGCAUGUCAUUAGCAUUGGAGCAAGUUUCAGUACAGAAGCAGAUUCUCAUCUAGUCUGUAUACAGAAUGAUGGAAUUUAUGAAACACAGGCCAACAGUGCCACUGGCCAUCCUAGAAAAGUGACAGGUGCAAGUUUUGUGGUAUUCAAUGGAGCUCUAAAAACAUCUUCAGGAUUUCUUGCUAAGUCCAGCAUAGUUGAAGAUGGCUUAAUGGUACAAAUAACUCCAGAGACCAUGAAUGGCUUGCGGCUAGCUUUACGAGAACAGAAAGACUUUAAAAUUACAUGUGGGAAAGUUGAUGCAGUAGACCUGAGAGAAUACGUGGAUAUCUGCUGGGUAGAUGCUGAAGAAAAAGGAAACAAAGGAGUUAUCAGUUCAGUGGAUGGAAUAUCAUUACAAGGAUUUCCAAGUGAAAAAAUAAAACUGGAAGCAGAUUUUGAAACCGAUGAGAAGAUUGUAAAAUGUACCGAGGUGUUCUACUUUCUAAAGGACCAGGAUUUAUCUAUUUUAUCAACUUCUUAUCAGUUUGCAAAAGAAAUAGCCAUGGCUUGUAGUGCUGCGCUGUGCCCUCACCUGAAAACUCUAAAAAGUAAUGGGAUGAAUAAAAUUGGACUCAGAGUUUCCAUUGACACUGAUAUGGUUGAAUUUCAGGCAGGAUCUGAAGGCCAACUUCUGCCUCAGCAUUAUCUAAAUGAUCUUGAUAGUGCUCUGAUACCUGUGAUCCAUGGUGGGACCUCCAACUCUAGUUUACCAUUAGAAAUAGAAUUAGUGUUUUUCAUUAUAGAACAUCUUUUUUAGUGAAAGAAUGUGCCAUAUUACAUAUUGCAACCUAAUUUGUUAAAACUAACUCCAGCACUAAAGCUGAAAUGCCACAAACACUAAAAGUAUAAAUAUGUCUGAUUUUUGAAACACAUAAGCUUUGCUCUUUAGGCAGGAAUGAUCUUUUCAAAUCAUUAGCACAAUAUUUAAAUAUCUAAAAAUUUAAGAGAUCCAUACUUUCUGUAGCUUUACAAUUAAUUUAAGUACUAAAAAGACAAGGAUUUCUUUUAAGAAAUUUAUAGCAUUUACUGUGUUAUUUAAAUGCUAAGCCAAAGUAUCUGCACUUAGGUAUACCUCUUUAUGCCAAUAAUGAUUUUAAUGAAGGCUCUUUUCAGAUGUAACCUUAUGAAGGAAAUAUCUGCUUUGUGUAUAUGCCAGUUAGAAUACUGGUUUCUAAAGUCUGUCAAAUUGUAUUUCAGUGGCACAAAAACCAGUUUUGAGGUCUUAGACUUAUAAUUCUUUGAAUAAAACUGAUAACUUAUUUGUAUAAUUGGAGUGGAGACCUACCUCCAUAAUUAGAUAAACUCUUUUUGGAUUAUAAUCAGAAUUUUGCCUUUUUUCUUCUCAAAUUAUUACAUAUGUAUGUAUUAUAUAUCCACAUAUAUAGUUUUCCCUGAUUAAAUGGAUAUUAAAAUAAUUGCGGGUGCUUCAGGACUUUUUGCUUCUAUAUUUAAGUAUAUUGUUUUUAUAGCAAGAACAUAUUCUGAAUGUUUUAUAAAUCUUUAAUAAUUUAUAUGUAGGUAAUAUUUUUGUAUCACAAUGCAUUAUUUUUUUCCUCCUUUCCUUCCAAACUAUACCACUGUAUUUACCACUUCUAAGAGUGACUGACGACGGGCCAGAUGACCCUUGAAGUAGUCAUUAUGUAGCAAUAAAUGAAGCCUGAAACAGGUUUUUUUACUUCCACUUUAAUCCUUAGAAAUUUCUUGGCAACUUCGCAUAUUUUCAUUGACACCAGUGUAUAAGUAUAAAUUUAAAUGAACUAAUUACUUUUGCAUAUUUUAAAUUCUUUAUAUGGUAGUUAUUUUUUAUAACAGGAUAUUAACAUAAGUUAAAUCCUAUGUAUUUGAAAUUGUUACAGAGCUUUCCUCUUUACUUCAAACAGCAAAAAAGUGGGGGGCAUAUUGUAGUCCUGUCAUUUAAGUUAUGUAAAAAAUUUAAUCAUUAUUUUGAUGCUUUAAACAUUCUCAUGUGUAAUAUAUGUUUUUGUAUCAAAAACACUCAUAUAUUUCAAGAAAAAGAAAUUAUGUUAAAUAGCCCUGUUUUAAGAAAAAUAUUUAUGAAGCAUCUCAACUUGAAGAUCAAGUCAAAGUUAUAACUCAGGAUCUGAGGUCUCAAGCUAGGAGAGACUGAGAAUUUUAAUCAGUUUGGGCAUAUAGUUUGGACUGAAUCACAUCUGUAGUACUUAGCCAAAGACAAUUUGGAGGAGAAUAUCAGCCUUCUGGAAGUAGCUACUUCCUGAACAAUGUAAAGUGUCGCAGAUAUUCAAUAAAAUGGCAACCUGUUAUAAUUUGUGAAAUUUAUUGAAAUGGUGUAAGAUGAAAACAAUUGCAUAUCAAACCCAAUUUAUGUUUUCUAAAUAUAGUGUAUGUAUUCUGCCAUGUAAGUAAUUGAACAGUCUUAAAAUAACCAAAUGGUAGAGGGCUGUUCCAUGAUGGGACAGCUUUGGAUUUGUUUUCAUAAAAUCUCUAUAUUCAAUAAAAAUUGGAAUUAUGUGCCUGAAGUUUGGAGGCACAUUUUGAAGUAUUCUUUGUAGACAUAUAGUAUGUUUCUGAAUGUGUUUGUUACUUAUUUGGUCAUUGGUACUUAAUUUGAAAUUUUAAUUUUUUAAGAGAAGAAAUAGAAUGGUUCUUUGUACUCAGUCUGCAAUGAUCUAUUUUUGGCUUAUGUCUUUUAAUACUACUCUCUUUCUCUGAAUUUUGAAAUAUGAAGUAAAAUCUAGCCCAUUUGUUUUAUGCAGCUAUUCAACAAACUUUGUGUGUUCGUAUACUUGCUACAUGCAGAGCACUUUACCAGGUUUCUAAGCAAAAAUUUCUAAAAAUGAUUAAUUGUUCUGACAGAAUUAGGCGUAGUUCUUUAUCAACAUUUAUGGAUUCCAUGCCACAAGUAGUAUGCGCUUAAGUGCAGAGCAUGCCAAGAGAAAGAGUAGGAUUUGGCCCUGUAGGAGCAAAGAUUCAAUUGUGGGAAACUACUUGUUUCUGAAAAUUGCAUGCUAGGAUAUUUACAUCAUGUUCCUGUUGAAAACAAUUCCUGAUUAAAAUACAAGAAUAAUCUUAAAACAUCAAAGAGAUUUUCCAGACAAUAAGGAAUGCCAAGUCCAAAAGUAAAGAGAAUAAGAGAAGCAAGCAUGUACCCUUACUCUGACAACCUUAUGAGUGAGGGGGACAGAAAUUAAAGUUCAGGGCCCAUAUAAGGUGAUGAACCUAACAGGAGACCCUCCACACAAUAGGCUGAGACUCCCAAAUACUUUCACCUUUAGGAUGAUAAUGAAUCAGAGGUGGAAGAACCAAUGUAAAAGAACAGGCAAGUUUAGAAUUGCCCCAGUGAUCUAAAGAAUCUUAAGCACUGAGCUUCCUUUAAGGUGUUCCCACACUAGUAAUGCCUCCAGGUGACAGAGAAAAUAAAAUGUAAAUACUUUUCAUGGAAAAGUAAUUUCAUUGUAGGCCUCAAAUUACUUUUCAAAUAUGUCUAGUAACACAUAGUAAAAAGUAGUCAUAUAAGGAAACUAGAUUCCAGAGGCAAGAAUUACUUGAAGCAAUGAAAACAAACUCACAGAUAUAGGUAUUAGAUUUGUUUUCUUUGUUUAAGGAAAUAAGGUGUGUGAAUGUACUUGCAGGAAAUGGGAAACUAUACGAUAAAAAGUUGUGGAGCUAAUCUGGAAAAGAACUGAAUAUAAACAUUACAAGAAUAUACAUAAAAACUGCACUUUAAAACUCAGUAAAUAGAUGUAAUAGAAUGUAGCCAAUUGGGGUAGUUUAUAAACUGGAAGAUAACUCAGGAGAAACUAUUCACAGUGCACCAUGGGAGAAACAGCUGGAAAAAAAAACAGAAGACCUGUAGAGAAUACAGUGAAAAAUCCUAAGUGCUUCAUUAGCUGUGAGAGGAGAGGCAAGAAUAGGACAGAGCAAAUACUUAGAUAGAAUGCAGAAUUUUAAAAACUGAUGAAAGACAUGACCCCACACAUUCUAGAAGCCAGACAAAUCCCAAACAGAAUAAACUAGAAAAUCCACACAUAGACACAUAAUAAGGCCAGGUGCAGUGGCUCACACCUGUAAUCGAGCACUUUGGGAGGCCAAGGCAGGAGGAUCACUCGAGCUCAGGUUGAGACCAGAGUGAGCAACACAGGGAGACACUGUCUCUGCAAAAUUAAAAAAAUUUUGCCAGGUGUGGUGGCUCAUACUUGUGGUCCCAGCUUCACGGGGGCUGAGGUGGGAGGAUCACUUGAGCCCAGGAGGUUAAGGCUCCAGUGAGCUGUGAUCGUGCAACAGAGCAAAACCUUGUCUCAAAAAAAAGGAAAAAGAAAAAAGACAUUUAACAGGAAAACUGGAAAUGCUAGCUGACAGAGAGAAAAAUAGUCCAAGGAACAAUUUGCUGUUUCUAGUCAGAGGACCAGAAAGGAGGUUGGAGGCUAUGGGACAAAACCCUUUUUAAUUUAAUUGCAGUAUUCUAAGAGAGCCUCAGGAAAGAUGCAGUAAGACCCACCGCCCCACCAGGAGAACCAUGGGUAAUGACUUGGAACCUUCUGGACUUUCCUUGCUCUACAUCAAUCCCGCAGCAGUAAAGAGGUAUCACUCUUCUCUUCCCCCUGGUGCACUAGUGGCAGACAUUGCAGGGCAGAACACUGGCAAUGGGGAGGCUAACGCCCUGACUUUCUAGCCAAAAACCAAGAAUGGGGUUCUAGAAACCAGAGUAUAGGUAAGAUCACAAAUAGGAGGGAACUGAAGAAAAGGAACCCUUAAAUCUGUCAAUAAAAUCCUGGGAUCAUCUCACAAGCUGUGUAUGUGUGAAACUAACCAGAAGCAGCUGAGCAAAGGUUCUGAACACUGAAUUACAGUGUAGGCCACUGUCCAAGUUUCAGAUUGGCCACUAGAUGGUGCACAACUGGGGCAAAGAACAGCUUAACAAAGGCAGUGAAAACUAACAUUGGAACCACAGCCACCAAAAAAAGUGGCCAGGAUGUGUGCUCUGAAACUUAACUGAAUUGAUGGUCUGCUAAAACAAAACAAAACAAAAACAUUCUUAUGAAGAUUUAAACAGGAUAGAGAAUAUCAUAAUAUUCCAAAUAUAUCCCAGAAACAACCCAAAAUGAUUGGACAAAGAACUUGUGAAACCUAAGCAACUCUCUAGGGAAAAGACAAUGAACAAGAGCCAACUCUAAGGUUACCCAAAUGUCAGAAUUAUCAGAAAAAGACUUAAAACUAGUUAUUUUAUUUUUUUUAUUUAUUUUUGAGACAGUCUCUAUCACCCAGGCUAGAGUGCAGUGAUACAAUCUUGGCUCACUGCAACCUCCACCCCCAGGGUGCAAGUGAUUCUCCUGUCUCAGCCUCCUGAGUAGCUGUGACUACAGGUGUGUACCACCACGCCUAGAUAAUUUUUUGUAUUUUUAAUAGAGACAGAGUUUCACCACGUUGGCCAGGCUGGUCUCAAACUCCUGACCUCAAGUGAUCUGCCUGCCUGGGCCUCCCAAAGUGCUGGGAUUACAGGCAUAAGCCAGCACACCUGGCCGUUAAACUAGUUAUUUUAAUCAUGCUACACAAAGAAGACAUUUCUCCAAAGGAAAUAUAUAAAGGGAAACACUGUUGAAAUAAAUGGAAAGCUAAAAGUCUCAGCAUAGAAGCUAUAAAAAGAAACAAGUGGAAAUUGUAGAACUGAAAAUACAAUAACAAAAUUUACUGGAAGGUCUCAACACAAUGAAGAUGACUGAGGGAAGAGUCAGUAAAUUUGAAGAUACAUGAGCAGAAAUUAUCUAGUCUGAAUGACAGAGAAAAAAGUGAAAAAAAUGAGAAGACCUUUGGGGAUCUGUGGGACAAUAUGAAACAGUCUAAUAUUCAUGUCUUAGGAGCCCAGAAAGAACAAUUGGAAGAAAAAAAUAUCUGAAGAAAUAAUAGCUAAAAACUUCCAAACAUCUGGCAAAAAACAAAUAUUCACAUACAUUUACAUAGCAUUCUAUUUAAAGCCGGUCUGCUGGCACAGCAAAUCCCAAAAAGGAAAACCACACCCAGGCACGUCAUAAUCAAAGUGAUGAAACCAACUGUAAAGAAAAUACUUUGAAAACAACUGGAAGAAAACAACACUUUGUAUAUAGGAGAACCAAAGAUUUCAGUGAUGGCAGAUUUCUCAUCAGAAACCAUGGAGCAACAUUUAUAAAGUGCUUUUAAAAAGCAACAAAACUGUCAACACAGAAUCCUUUAUCCAGCAAAUAUAUUCUUUAGGAAAGAAAAUGAAAUAAAGACAUUUUCUUUUUUUUCUUUACUUUUUUUUUUUUUAUGAGAUGGAGUCUCACUCUGUUGCCCAGGCUGGAAUGGAUUGGUGCGAUCUCAGCUCACUGCAACCUCCGCCUCCCGGUUCAAGCAGUUCUCCUGUCUGAGCCUCCAGAGGAGUAGCUGGGAUUACAGGUGCGUGGUACCACGCCCAGCUAAUUUUUUUAUGUUUGUAGUAGAGACGAGUUUCACCAUGUUGGUCAGGAUGGUCUCAAACUCCUGACCUCAGGUGAUCUGCCUGCUUCGGCCUCCCAAAGUGCUGAGAUUAGAGGCAUGAGCCACCAUACCUGGCUGAAAUAAAGACAUUGUCAGAAGAAGGAAAGCUAAAAUAAUUCAUUGCUAGUAGUCCUCCUUUAACAGAAAUGGUAAAGGAAGUUCAUGGGGAAGGAAAAUGAUUGCAAAGAAGGAAGAGCAACCAAAAUGGCAAAUCUCUGGAUAAACCAAAUAGACUUACAUGUUUGUUAAAAUAUAUGUAACUGCUGAAAUAAAAAAAUUGUAACAUCA